AGAUGGAUUCUUACUCUGUAGCCAGGCUGGAGUGCAAUGGUGCGAUCUCGGCUCACUGCAACCUUCGCCUCCCAGGUUCAAGCGAUUCUCCUGCUUCAGCCUCCCGAGUAGCAGGGACUACAGAUGCACGCCACCACGCCCAGCUACUUUUUGUAUUUUUAGUAGAGAUGGGGUUUCACCAUGUUGGCCAGGAUGGUCUUGAUCUCUUGACGUUGUGAUCCGCCCGCCUUGGCCUCCCAAAGUGCUGGGAUUACAGGUAUGAGCCACCACGCACCACGCCCCGUCACUUUUGCCCAUUUUUUAAUUGGCUUAAUGUGAUCCAAAGUUUACUACAGUAGCCCCCCCUUAUCUGUGGGGGAUAUUUUCCAAGAUCCCCAGUGAAACAAGAUAGUACCAAACCCAGUUGCUGUCAAUCAGAACAUCUGUUUUGUCUUCUACCCACAAACUUAUUUGUUUAUUUAUUGGUUUUGUUUUGUUUUGUUGUUGUUGUUGUUUUCUGAGAUAGAAUCUCACUCUGUCACCCAGGCUGGAGUGUAAUGGCGCAGUCUCGGCUCACUGCAACCUCUGCCACCCGAGUUCAAGCAAUUCUCGUGGCUCAGCCCCUCCCAAGUAGCUGGGACUACAGGUGCCCACCACCACACCUCGUUAAUUUUUUUUUUUUUUUUUUAGUAGAGAUGGGAUUUCGCAUGUUGGCCAGCCUGGUCUUGAACUCCUGACCUCAAGUGAUCUGCCGGCCUCAGCCUCCCAAAGUGCUGGGAUUACAGGCAAAGUCCUGGGAUUACAGAUGUGAGCCCCUGUGCCAGGCCCCAGCCACAAAUUUAAUGCCUUUUCCAUCUUAAAGUUUGACAUGUGACAGCAAAACUAGCAUGAAAUUAUUUUCCUUCUUCAGUUUCACAGAUGGAAGAUUCGUUCUUACAUCUUAGCAACCUCAGCGUAUGAUACUUAGUAAGUCGAGAACUUUCACCUUUUCACUUAAAGGAAGCACUCAAUGGCUUCUCUUUGGCAUAUCUGAAUGGCCAACAUCACUGUUGGUGUGUUUUGGGCCAUUAAGUAAAAUAAAGGUGACUUGAAAUGAGCACGUCGAUCCCACGACACUUGAGCUGACGAUCAAGACAGCACAGGUGAGUGGGCGGGAGCAUGCUCGGCGCGAACGUGCCGGACGGGGCUCGUGUCUCGAGCUGGACAGAGUGAGAUUUCAUCACCUUACUCAGAACAGCAUGCGGUUUAAAACUGACGAAUUGUUUGUUUCUGGAAGUUUCCAUUUAAUAUUUUCUGACCUUGGUUGACUGCGGGUGAUUGAAAUCACAGUGGAACUGCCGAUAAGUAGGGGAUUUCUGUAAUAGGUAACAAAUUGGAUCCAGGUCAGUGGGUUCAGUUUUCAAACACUUUAGUUACCCCAAUGUUAAGAUUUGGGGUAUUUCUAAUAAAAAAAGGAAUGUUUGGCAGACAUUUUUCUGCACCUGGAGCUGUGGGGCCUGCUCUCUGGAGAGAGAGGCUGGACGGCCCUACCCCGUGGCGCCAUCCUUUUGCGGGUUUGCGCAUCCCUCUCAGCGGGCAGCAAGCCUCAGCUCAUAGCCUGGCCUCCUUUUUGUUUUUGUGGCCAGUGAACAGCUUUUACAUUUUUUAAUGGCUGGAAGAAAGUAAUUUGUAGGAGGUGAAAAUGUUAUGAAAUUCAAAUUUCAGUGACCAUAUUAAAGUUCUUUUGGAACACAGCCGUGCUCAUUAGUUCAUACUCCAACUGUGGUUGAGUUGUAGUGACAGAGACCUCAUGGCCCGUAAGUGCCCCAGAUAUUUCCUGUCUGACCCUUUAUGGGGAAUGUGUAACAGCAAACAGCAGUGAGGCACACAGGCUAUAAUUGGGAAAGAUGUUCUGGAACCUUGGUAUCGAACAUCCAGUGAAGGUAAUGAACAUAUUCAGGAAAAAAGUACUAGUGUUUUCAUGUGUCUGAUUAUUUACUGUUUCUUCAUUGUGUACAAAUAAAUAAUUAAAAAGGAAACAGUAAGUUUUAGGGUGGUAAAUUUCCGACCUCCUUCUCAUAAGUCGCGAUAAUUUCCUAUCUGCAUGAGAAUAAAGUUAAGCUCCUAGGAGAUACAUAAACUUAUUUCUUCAAAAUGUAAAAUUCACAGAUAAAUUUUAAGUCCGAUGUUAAUUCUGAAUCCAUGUAGAUAGAUUUUUAGUAUUCCAGUCACUUCUGUAAUUCUUUUUUUUUUUUUUUUUUCCUUCAGACGGAGUCUUGCUCUGUCGCCCAGGCUGGAGUGCAGUGGUGCGAUAUCGGCUCGCUACAAACCCUGCCUCCCGGGUUCAUGCCAUUCUCCUGCCUCAGCCUCCUGAGUAGGUGGGACUACAGGCGCCCACCACCACGGUUGGCUAAUUUUUUGUAUUUUUAGUAGAGACGGGGUUUCAAAUAACCCUGUUUUUACAAUCUCAUGUAGUUUCUCAUAUAUAUAUAUUAGAAUAAACUAUAUAUACUAUGUAUAUAGUCACACAAAGCUGGAUUCAUUUAAGUAGUAUACAGAAUAUAUGCAAUUAAUUCAGUGCUACAAUUGCCCAUCUAUCUUUUAAUCCAUUCCAGUCAAAACAUAAGCGUGUAUAUUUGAAUUAAUAUUCAUUUGAUUUAAAUUUAAAAUAAAAACAACCGGAUUGUCUUAGGUGUUUCAGUGGAGGAGAUGAGAAGACAGAUUUCCUAUUCUUGGACUCAUUUUAAUUUGUGAUAUUGAUGUAACUCAUGCCAGAACUUCAGCUUAAAUCACGAUUAUGAAAUAAUUGUGUGACCUUUCUUUUAGCAGAGACAGGAAAAUGUCUAAAGGACUUCAGAAUUUUGUGAGAAUAUGCUUCAAAUCUUUGAAAAAUAUUCUUCACGGACGUGUUUAUAUGUAAAUAAGUCUGUUGACAUUAGUGUUUCCAUGAAGGGAUACCCUGUUCUCCUGAGUAGAAGCUGUGAGGCAUCCCUGUUUUGACUCUGCCAUUGAAUAUUAGUCCUGGUUUAAAUUCUCCUAAUAUUUCACGCAUGCACUAAAAGGGGGCUUAACCCCUUUAAAAAAUAAAUGGAUAGAGGAAGAGUAUAUGUCAGAUAUAACAUGAAAUUCAGGGUACGUUCUCUUAGGAAUUUAAGACUUGGAUUUCAAGUGACUUAGACAGCUUUGUUAUGAAAGGUAUGCUGGGAUCAACCUAGUUUUUAAGUUUUUCUUUGACUCUGUUUUCUGAUCUACCAGAAUAGGUGAUGGUCACUUGUCUAAUGAAGAAAUAGUGAUGAAGUGUUGCAAACAGUGAGGAAGCCCUCUCAAGGCCAGUGCCUCCUACGCAUUGUGCGCCAGCGCCUCCUACGCGGUGUGCCCCGGCACCUCCCACGCGGUGUGCCCCGGCGCCUCCCACGCGGUGUGCCCCGGCGCCUCCCACGCGGUGUGCCCCGGCGCCGGCUCUGCUGCUAGUGUCCUCCUUCAGGCCAAAAGAGCCCUGUGUCCCUGGGGCCCAUGGUGGCCACAGCUGUGGCUCAGCCGUCAUUCCUUUCGUGGCAAGAGUCCUUAUUUUACACUGUUAAGAGUUUUAGGUGACAUAAGAAAGCAACAAUUUGCCAUAGCUCUGGUAGACAACACCAUUUGAUUUGUGGUGAGAAAGUCAAGGAGUGACCAUGAUCACUACCUGUGGUCUCAGUUAAAAACUUCAGGGAUAUUAGUGUCUUUUCGGAUUUCCUAGUGAAAUUUCUCAUUAAUGUAAAAAGCACCUGGGGAGAAUUUUGAAAAUGUUUUCUGUUAAGAAAUGACCUUAAACAGAUGGAUUUUUAAGCAGUGUCAUUGCACCAAAGCAUUAGGGUAUCCAGUUACUCUGUUGCAGUAAUCGAAGCCCAUAAACCACAGAGAAAAUUACAACCUUGUGGAUUUUGGAAAAGAUCAAUUGCUUUAUUUACUGUGUGAAUUAAUUGAUGGCCUGCUUUUUAUGUAGACUAGAAAUAGAUAAAAAUGGUUAUCUUCUGCAAUUUCCUUUUACUAUUGGAGGUAGUAAUUUGACCAUACUGUGACAGCUUAUUACAGGGUUGACAGAUGUUUUUAGAUUCCUCUCUACCUUUUUAACCUUGACUACUUUCUUUGUAGAAGCAACUAUUUGGAUAAAGCAUCCUAAUAUCUUUGAAAAAAAUACCAUUUAAUCAAGAUUUCUAACCUGCUUUUUCAGUUUCCAUGAAUACUGACCAAAGUCUCUAGAGAAGACAGGCAGAUAGGAUUUGAGGAUCUUGAGGAGGGACAGAUAGUUUGGGAGAUGAGUAAAGACAUUUGAUUAUACAAAGAUCAGAAGGCACAAAUUUGUGUUGGUACCAAAUUAUAUUUAAGUCACUCUACUGCUAAGUUCAGCAGCCCAGCUGUGGGGACGAGCAGAGAUCCCCACUGAUGUGGAGAGCUAACAAGUGCUCCGUCAGAUCCUCGUGCCUUACAGUUCUAAACAUUGAAGCGCCGUGUGCCUGGAAGUCUCGUCCACUGUCAGGAAUACUGUCCCUAAUACUUUUUCUCAUCGUAAUCUGAUAAUAUGAAGAGGUGGCUCUGAGUUGCUUUUCCCCAGGCCCCACAGAAGUGCUUCUCUUCCCUCCAGUGCAGGACACCAGCUUUCUUGGAAAGCACUGAAUGAGGCCUUGGGUUUUUCAUGCACCUCACCCUUCUCGGCAGCUUGUGUUUUUCACGCGCCUCACCUUUCUCAACAGUUUGGGUUUGUCACACACCUCACCUUUCUCGGCAGUUUGGGUUUAUCAAGCGCCUCACUUUUCUCAGCAGUUCGGGUUUGUCACGCGCCUCACCCUUGUCAACAGUUUGGGUUUGUCACGUGCCUCACUUUUCUCAGCACUUUGGGUUUGUCACGCGCCUCACCUUUCUCAGCACUUUGGGUUUGUCACACACCUCACCUUUCUCGGCAGUUUGGGUUUAUCACACGCCUCACCCUUCUCGGCAGUUUGGGUUUGUCGCGCGCCUCACUUUUCUCAGCAGUUUGGGUUUGUCACGCGCCUCACCCUUCUCGGCAGUUUGGGUUUGUCACACACCUCACCUUUCUCGGCAGUUUGGGUUUGUCACGUGCCUCACUUUUCUCAACAGUUUGGGUUUGUCACUCGCCUCACCCUUCUCAACGGUUUGGGUUUGUCACGCGCCUCACCCUUCUCGGCGGUUUGGGUUUGUCGCGCGCCUCACCCUUCUCGACGGUUUGGGUUUGUCGCGCGCCUCACCCUUCUCGGCGGUUUGGGUUUGUCGCGCGCCUCACCCUUCUCGGCGGUUUGGGUUUGUCGCGCGCCUCACCCUUCUCGGCGGUUUGGGUUUGUCGCGCGCCUCACCCUUCUCGACGGUUUGGGUUUGUCGCGCGCCUCACCCUUCUCGACGGUUUGGGUUUGUCGCGCGCCUCACCCUUCUCGGCGGUUUGGGUUUGUCGCGCGCCUCACCCUUCUCAACAGUUUGGGUUUGUCGCGCGCCUCACCCUUCUCGACGGUUUGGGUUUGUCGCGCGCCUCACCCUUCUCGACGGUUUGGGUUUGUCGCGCGCCUCACCCUUCUCGACGGUUUGGGUUUGUCGCGCGCCUCACCCUUCUCGGCGGUUUGGGUUUGUCGCGCGCCUCACCCUUCUCCGUGGUUUGGGUUUGUCGCGCGCCUCACCCUUCUCGACGGUUUGGGUUUGUCGCGCGCCUCACCCUUCUCAACGGUUUGGGUUUGUCACGCGCCUCACCCUUCUCGGCGGUUUGGGUUUGUCGCGCGCCUCACCUUUCUCAGCAGUCCCCAAGUCCUGGCUGCUCCAGGAAGGUGUUCUGUGUGUGUUAGAACCUUGGACUCCCUUUUGUUGUGCUGUGUGUGAACCAAAAUUUUCUGGGCAGUUUUAACUUUCUGCAAGUCUUUCUGACCAUUUGCGCUGACUUUAAUUCAUAUUCAGAGAGAACAAUAUAAAACAUUUUAAAUAUUUAACGUUUUUAGUAUUUCUCCAGACUGAAUUAUUUGAACGCAGGCCACAUCUGUUUAAGUAAACCUGUAGUAUGCUGAGUGCUUCCAAGUAAGGGUGUGUUGCUUGCCUAAAGGCUUCUAGAAACCAGAGUUUCCGAUUUCUAUUGUGAUGUAACUGAUAAAGAAGAGGCGUCUCAUGUUCUUGUAGAACCGAGGUUCUCUGGUCCUUUUUGCCUUAUCUGUUCCAUUUUUGAGACUGUGUUGAUUUUACACAAGGAAACAAAGCUACCCGCUUAGAUGUUGUUCAUUUUAUAGGCUUAACGUAGAACUAGCCAAGUGGUGUAGGAACGUUGGUGUUUUCAGAUGGCCAGUAAAUGGGUGACCCUCUCACUUAGGUGUGCUCCGGGGAACGGCGCGUUGGCCCCCACCUAUGCUGGUGGGGCCUGCCCCAGGGCACACUCUCGAUUGCUGUGCCAGGGACUCAGAUUCCUUCUUCCUUCCCCUUUAGUUGUGGUCUAAGAGAGGGAAAGAAUUCUUCCUUGCAACCAACCAUUGCUUCCAGUAAGAAUUUUGUGUGUUUUGUUUUUUUCUUUUUAAAAUAGUGCCUAAAGGGUUAUGCAGCAUUGAGCAAAGCUCAAAUCCUUCUUGGAAUGAGGAAGAAUCUUGAAUAAAUGAACUUGAUUGGCAAGUUCAUGAUUUCAUGUUUAGUGGCAUUUUGUUUCUAAAAGAAUCAUUUUAUCCAUUUAUCUUUUAAAUUUUACUUAAAGGUAUUAAAUCAGCAAUGCCUCAGGUGUAGCAUCUUUCUUCAUAUUGUCUCAGACAUUACCUAUCUAAACUUAUUCUAGGCUAUUAAUUUUUAAAGAGGAAUGAGUCAGCAGAAUUGAUACUGCAUGUUUCAGUGUUACUAAUGUUAAUGGAAUUUUAAAAUAACUCCUCUACAUUCCCUGUCAAGUGCCUGCUGUACUUUUUUUUGUAAUUAAAAGUGCUUAUAUCAGCCUGGUGUGGUGGCUCAUGCCUGUAAUCCCAGCACUUUUAGAGCCCGAGGCAGAGGGAUCACUUGAGGCCAGGAGUUUGAGACCAGCGUGGCCAACAUGGCAAAACCCUGUCUCUACUAAAACUACAAAAAUUAGCCACUUGUGGUGGCGGGCACCUGUAGUCCCAGCUACUCGAGAGGCAGGAGAAUUGCUUGAACCCGGGAGGAGGAGGUUGUAGUGAGCUGAGAUCGUGCCACUGCACUCCAGCCUGAGUGACGGAGUUAGACUCCAUCUCAAAAAAAAAAAUGCUUAUAUCGUGCAUAGGACAUGGAAUUUAUGAACAAUAAAAUCCUGUGCAAGUUCUGAUUGUUAAUACUGGUCUUCAAGGGGAAUGUUGUUUGAAGAAAGACAUUCCUUUUACUUAAUUUUUGUUUUAAAUGUUAGCUGUCAAUUUUUUUAUGUUUGGAUAUAGGAAGAAUAUGAUUUAAUUGGCAAGAAAAUUUUGACCAGUUAUGUCAAUUCCAUCCUGUAUACUUCAGCAGGGCAUAGCAGGAAGGACUCUGGAGUCCUUUGGGUCUGGAUCUCUUUAUUCUACCUGUUCCCCCGAGGCGUUUUGUUUUCUGUUAGAUGGAGCCACUAAUUGUUCAAAGGUUCUGGUGAGGAUUAAACAAAAUAUUGUAUGUAGAGUUCCUGGAGCACAGUUAAAUGUUCUGUCUUUGUAUAUUUGGUUUAAUUUUUCUAAACAAAACAACUUUGGUAAUAGCAGCGUAUUAGAAUCUAAAAUACGCCUUUGUUCUUUUAAAAGAUAACAUUAAAGAGAUUUUUGCGGGUGGUGUCAACUCAAAUAUAAUAGAAACGUGAAUAAUCGUACAAUGAUUAUUUCUAGUUCAUACAGAUAAUAUAAAUAUUGAAAUUUGUUUUAUAAUUAGAACUUAAGAGAGAUUUGAGUCUUUAAGUUGAAAGAUAAGAUUUAAAACCGAAUCUGUGUUCCUGUGUUCCUGUGUGAUUGAGGACUGUGUUUUCUGUGAUCCCUGUGUGUCCCAGUCUUUCUCUGUGAUGUUUUUGCUACUUUAGAUUCUGUUUUAUGCAAAAUAAGCAAAUGUUUAUGAAUAUGUAUUAGCGAGAAGCAGAUUUUUGACUUAGUGAACAGAAUUUAAAAUUUCGUAACAGAUUUGCUUUGUUCAAAUCUGAUAUAUUCUCUUUCUCUUUUUCUUUAGCACAUUGGGAUAAUCACUCAUAGAUGAAAAACCUCAGAACUAUUGAAUGCCUUGGGAUAACACUACUAAGAGACGGCUCGAUUUUCAAAGCCACUUUGUGUUCAUUUUCCAGACACUGAAAGAGCAGAAUGGCUAAAUAAGACUGUAAAACACAUGUGGCCUUUCAUUUGCCAAUUUAUAGAGAAGUUGUUUCGAGAAACUAUAGAACCAGCCGUGCGGGGAGCAAACACCCACCUUAGCACCUUUAGUUUCACGAAGGUCGACGUGGGCCAGCAGCCCCUCAGGAUCAAUGGUGUUAAGGUAUACACUGAAAAUGUAGACAAAAGGCAAAUUAUUUUGGACCUUCAGAUUAGUUUUGUAGGAAAUUGUGAGAUUGAUUUGGAGAUCAAACGAUAUUUUUGUAGAGCUGGUGUGAAAAGUAUCCAGAUUCAUGGUACCAUGCGGGUGAUCCUGGAACCGUUGAUUGGAGAUAUGCCCUUAGUUGGAGCUUUGUCUAUCUUCUUCCUUAGGAAACCACUUUUAGAAAUUAACUGGACAGGACUGACGAAUCUUCUGGAUGUCCCUGGAUUGAAUGGUUUAUCAGAUACUAUCAUUUUGGAUAUAAUAUCAAACUAUCUGGUGCUUCCCAAUCGAAUCACCGUUCCACUUGUCAGUGAAGUUCAAAUAGCUCAGUUGCGGUUUCCUGUACCAAAGGGUGUUCUAAGGAUACAUUUUAUUGAAGCUCAGGAUCUUCAGGGGAAAGACACUUACCUUAAGGGACUUGUCAAGGGAAAGUCAGACCCCUAUGGAAUCAUUAGAGUUGGCAACCAAAUCUUCCAAAGCAGAGUCAUCAAGGAGAACCUCAGUCCAAAGUGGAAUGAAGUCUAUGAGGCUUUAGUGUAUGAACAUCCUGGACAAGAAUUAGAGAUUGAGCUCUUUGAUGAAGACCCAGACAAGGAUGACUUUUUAGGAAGUCUUAUGAUUGACCUCAUUGAAGUUGAAAAGGAGCGCCUUUUAGAUGAAUGGUUCACUCUGGACGAGGUUCCCAAGGGGAAGCUACACUUGAGACUGGAGUGGCUCACGUUAAUGCCAAAUGCGUCAAACCUCGACAAGGUGCUAACAGACAUCAAAGCUGACAAAGACCAAGCCAACGAUGGUCUUUCCUCUGCAUUGCUGAUCUUGUACUUGGAUUCAGCAAGGAACCUUCCGAGUAACCCAUUAGAAUUUAACCCCGAUGUCUUGAAGAAGACUGCAGUUCAGAGAGCUUUAAAGUCAGGGAAGAAAAUAAGCAGCAACCCAAAUCCUGUUGUCCAGAUGUCAGUUGGGCACAAGGCCCAGGAGAGCAAGAUUCGAUACAAAACCAAUGAACCUGUGUGGGAGGAAAACUUCACUUUCUUCAUUCACAAUCCCAAGCGCCAGGACCUUGAAGUUGAGGUCAGAGACGAGCAGCACCAGUGUUCCCUGGGGAACCUGAAGGUCCCCCUCAGCCAGCUGCUCACCAGUGAGGACAUGACUGUGAGCCAGCGCUUCCAGCUCAGUAACUCGGGUCCAAACAGCACCAUCAAGAUGAAGAUUGCCCUGCGGGUGCUCCAUCUCGAAAAGCGAGAAAGGCCUCCAGACCACCAACACUCAGCUCAAGUCAAACGUCCCUCUGUGUCCAAAGAGGGGAGGAAAACAUCCAUCAAAUCUCAUAUGUCUGGGUCUCCAGGCCCUGGUGGCAGCAACACAGCUCCAUCCACACCAGUCAUUGGGGGCAGUGAUAAGCCUGGUAUGGAAGAAAAGGCCCAGCCCCCUGAGGCCGGCCCUCAGGGGCUGCACGACCUGGGCAGAAGCUCCUCCAGCCUCCUGGCCUCCCCAGGCCACAUCUCAGUCAAGGAGCCGACCCCCAGCAUCGCCUCGGACAUCUCGCUGCCCAUCGCCACCCAGGAGCUGCGGCAAAGGCUGAGGCAGCUGGAAAACGGGACGACCCUGGGACAGUCUCCACUGGGGCAGAUCCAGCUGACCAUCCGGCACAGCUCGCAGAGAAACAAGCUUAUCGUGGUCGUGCAUGCCUGCAGAAACCUCAUUGCCUUCUCUGAAGACGGCUCUGACCCCUAUGUCCGCAUGUAUUUAUUACCAGACAAGAGGCGGUCAGGAAGGAGGAAAACACACGUGUCAAAGAAAACAUUAAAUCCAGUGUUUGAUCAAAGCUUUGAUUUCAGUGUUUCGUUACCAGAAGUGCAGAGGAGAACGCUCGACGUUGCCGUGAAGAACAGUGGCGGCUUCCUGUCCAAAGACAAAGGGCUCCUUGGCAAAGUAUUGGUUGCUCUGGCAUCUGAAGAACUUGCCAAAGGCUGGACCCAGUGGUAUGACCUCACGGAAGAUGGGACGAGGCCUCAGGCGAUGACAUAGCCGCAGCAGGCAGGAGGCGUCCUCUUCAGCGUAGCUCUCCACCUCUACCCGGAACACACCCUCUCACAGACGUACCAAUGUUAUUUUUAUAAUUUCAUGGAUUUAGUUAUACAUACCUUAAUAGUUUUAUAAAAUUGUUGACAUUUCAGGCAAAUUUGGCCAAUAUUAUCAUUGAAUUUUCUGUGUUGGAUUUCCUCUAGGAUUUCGCCAGUUCCUACAACGUGCAGUAGGGCGGCGGUAGCUCUUGUGUCUGUGGACUCUGCUCAGCUGUGUCCGUAGGAGUCGGAUGUGUCUGUGCUUUAUUAUGGCCUUGUUUAUAUAUCACUGAGGUAUACUAUGCCAUGUAAAUAGACUAUUUUUUAUAAUCUUUACAUGCUGGUUUAAAUUCAGAAGGAAAUAGAUCAAGGAAAUAUAUAUAUUUUCUUCUAAAACUUAUUAAAUUCGUGUGACAAAUAAUCAUUUUCAUCUUGGCAGCAAAAAGUUCUCAGUGACCUAUUUUGUGGUGUUUCUUUUUGAAAAGAAAAGCUGAAAUAUUAUUAAAUGCUAGUAUGUUUCUGCCCAUUAUGAAAGAUGAAAUAAAGUAUUCAAAAUAUUAACAUUUUCAUAAAUAUAAGGAUGUAUUAUUGAGAAGUAAGUUGAAGGGCUUAUAAGGAAAAAUGUUUUAUAACUGAGUAAUAUAUUAAGAGAAUUGUCAUGGUUCAUAAAUCACAUUAUGCUAAUCUGAAAUUUCUUACAUAAAAAUGAAGUGUCUUAUGUUUAUUUUAAUUGCUGUUGUAACUUACUCAUGAAACAGUAUACAGACACCUUGUACUUUUCCUCAACUGUAAGAGCAGACUUUCAAUGUUAGCAAUUAAGCUGUUGUCAAACAAUCAGUCAUGAGCUUUGUUAAUUUUCAAUGUUUUCCCAGCCUAUAAAAAAAGGAAGGUACACGUUGUCCUUUUAAAGGUUGUGAGGUAGAUUGGAGUGAGUAGACAGGAUAUUGCAUUAAAAAUUGAAAGCUCGAUCUCAUUAUUGUCAGGAACCCCCAGUGUGACCUCACACAUAGGAUGUGGGACCUUUGAGCCGAUGUGCACUGGCCACCACCAGGGUUGGGGGCGCCACAGCUGCGAGCCCGGCCCCUGCUGUUCUCAGCAGCCACUUCCCAGGCUGCCUCACUUUAUGCCAUGACUGACCUUAAUAUUGGGAUAUUGUUAUGCAAUUUUUAUCCUGUUUAGACUGUUAAAAGCAGGUUUCUGUACUUAAGAGUCCCCCAGACCUCCUGUGAGGUGAGGCUCUGUUGCAGUGUCGUAGGCUGUGUGUGUCUGUAAAGAAAGAAUGCACAUAUGUAGACGAUUAAGUGUAUAUUAUAAGCUAUAUGCUGAAAAUGGCUUCCAUAGCCAUGAGAACAUCUUAAAACUAUGUGUAAAUAUAUUAAGGAAAGUAUAGCUUUGUAAUUUAAAUUGGAGCUUUUAGCUUGUUUCAUGGAACUAUACAACUUGUGGGUAACUCACAUGACCAAACAAACCAAAGUGCCUGUGACGGGGCGGGUGGCGUCUACCCACCCUCCCUUCUAGCAGAUUCUUAUUUUGUUUGAAUUUAUAAACAAGGCUGGUGGCUGUCUACCCACCCUCCCUUCUAGCAGAUUUUGAUUUUGUUUCAAUUUAUAACUUACACUUUGAACCAUGGGUUUACUUAUAAUGGAGUCUGUAGCUUCACAGCAUAUUUCAUGUAAUCAUAAAGACCAGUAUAUUCCCUCCUGCUGAAUGACAUGCGACUGUAAAGCCUCUUUAUAAACCAUUUCCAAUGUUAGUAUAUAGGAUUAUUUGGGAAGCGUAUCAAUACCUUUAUAGACAAAUACGAACAUGUAUGCACACAAAACAUUUAACUAUGGUAUUUAUGGAAGACAGGUAACAACAUUAAAUCUAGUUGCUUUCCCUUAGUAUUAGAUUUGUUGAGGGUUUUUUAAAAAUCAGGUCUGUUGAAAGUCUUCUGUCAUAAUCUAUAAAGCAGCAGCACUCAUGGAAAUUGUAGCAUGCCAGUAAUUUUUACCAACAUCCCAUACAUCUGAGUUCUGCAGUCCAGUGUGUAAUCCGCUCCAUGUGUAUUUUGCUUAAUGGAAUGCUUUAUUUAAGCACUUAGGCAGAGUAGACACAAUUAAAGGUACAAAGCCCAGAGGAAGUGGUAGAGCAGCACCGUGCCUGCCCUGAGGCAGUGGAGUCAGUAGCGCUGUCCCCAGGGCCUUGAGUGCCUGGAGGUGCUUGGCCUCCAGUAGCUGCCUCCAUUCUCUUUUAAAAAAAGGGGGUGAUUCUGAGGCACUGAAGUGCCUCCCAGAUGUGGAGGAGUGAAGCCACCAUCGAGGCCACACUCAGCACUCCAGGAUCCCAGCGAUGUCAGACACUCUUGAGUUGUCAAAACGUUAAUUUUCAGUUUUAAAUAAUCAGUUUAUCUAAGAAAAGGGAAUUUUAACUUUUCUACCUUGAGCCAAGCCAAUGAAGGGAAAAUUAAUUAACUUAGUAAAUUUGAAGUGCAGCUCUGUUAGCUCGUACAUGUGGGUUCUUAUCCUGAUCCUGUGCCUUAAAGUAGGAAGGUGUUUCCAAGUUCAGAUUAAAAUAGAAGCAGCUGGCCGGGUGCGGUGGCUCACGCCUGUAAUCCCAGCACUUUGGGAGGCCGAGGCGGGCGGAUGACCUGAGGUCAGGAGUUCAAGACCAGCCUGGCCAACAUGGAGAAACCCCAUCUUUACUAAAAAUACAAAAAUUAGCCGGGCGUGGUGGUGGAGCGCACGCCUGUAGUCCCAGCUACUCGGGAGGCUGAGGCAGGAGAAUUGCUUGAACCCAGGAGGCGGAGGUUGCAGUGAGCCAAGAUCGCACCACUGCACUCCAGCCUGGGCAACAGAGUGAGACUCCGUCUCAAAAAAUAAAUAAAAUAGAAGCAGCCUUGUAACUGUAUUUACCAUGAUAAUAUAUUCUGCACGGUAAGAAUUCCUUUUACAGACAUUCUUUAUCAAGAGGUCGGCCCUUCUUUUUCAGGCACAUAAGCCAAAUGCAGGCCUGUGUGUAGCUGUGUGUUUUUUCUGUGGUUGCCGCAUUUAUUCCACCUCCAGCUGGACCCCCCACUGCAAAUAGAGAACAGCGGUGGGGGAUGGGGGUUAAAAAGUAGAGAACCUCCUUUCUGUUCAACUAAUUUCACGUGACAGUGCAUGUAUUUAUUCAAUAAAACCUUUAUGUUAGCUCA